AGAUCGAGGCUGCCUCCCCCUCUCAGCCGGCAGCACAUUCCGUCGCCUUGCCGCCGCCCGGCCCCACAGUUGUCUUUGCCGGAGCUGCAGUCGCGCUGGGGUUAGGGCGGGGGGGCGGGCGGGGAGAGGAGAAGGCCGCGGCGGAGGCAGGUGAGAGGAGGAAGGAAGCGGCGGCGCGGCGGGCACAGCAGCUCAGGCGGCGGCCCGGUUCCUGGGAGUGUCGGUGCGGCGCGUUGGUUGGGGCGGAUCCCGCGGGGCCCGGGCGGGGGAAGGAGUCACCGGCCCGGCCAUGGCGGACAACGAGAAACUGGACAACCAACGGCUCAAGAAUUUCAAGAACAAAGGCCGCGACUUGGAGACUAUGAGAAGACAACGAAAUGAAGUUGUAGUUGAAUUAAGGAAGAAUAAAAGAGAUGAACAUCUCUUAAAGAGAAGGAAUGUACCACAUGAAGAUAUCUGUGAAGACUCUGAUAUAGAUGGUGAUUAUAGAGUGCAAAAUACCUCUCUAGAAGCUAUUGUUCAAAAUGCUUCAAGUGAUAACCAAGGAAUUCAAUUAAGUGCAGUUCAAGCUGCUAGGAAGCUUUUGUCCAGUGAUCGAAAUCCACCAAUUGAUGACUUAAUAAAAUCUGGAAUAUUGCCCAUUUUAGUCCAUUGUCUUGAAAGAGAUGACAAUCCUUCUUUACAGUUUGAAGCUGCAUGGGCUUUGACAAACAUUGCAUCUGGAACUUCUGAACAAACUCAAGCAGUAGUUCAGUCCAAUGCUGUGCCACUUUUCCUGAGGCUUCUCCAUUCACCCCAUCAGAAUGUCUGUGAGCAAGCAGUGUGGGCAUUGGGAAAUAUCAUAGGUGAUGGGCCCCAGUGUAGAGAUUAUGUCAUAAGUCUUGGAGUUGUGAAACCUUUACUUUCCUUCAUAAGUCCAUCUAUUCCUAUAACAUUCUUAAGAAAUGUUACUUGGGUUAUGGUCAACUUAUGUCGCCACAAAGACCCACCACCACCAAUGGAAACCAUUCAGGAGAUUCUUCCAGCCCUUUGUGUUUUAAUUCAUCACACAGAUGUAAAUAUACUGGUAGACACAGUCUGGGCCCUCUCUUACCUUACUGAUGCUGGCAAUGAACAAAUACAGAUGGUAAUAGACUCUGGAAUAGUUCCUCAUUUGGUUCCUCUGCUCAGCCACCAGGAAGUUAAAGUUCAGACUGCUGCACUUAGAGCUGUGGGCAACAUUGUUACUGGAACUGAUGAGCAAACACAAGUAGUUUUGAACUGUGAUGCUCUUUCACACUUCCCAGCACUCCUGACACAUCCCAAAGAGAAAAUUAAUAAAGAAGCAGUGUGGUUCCUCUCCAACAUCACUGCAGGAAAUCAGCAGCAGGUACAGGCAGUAAUUGAUGCCAAUCUUGUACCAAUGAUAAUACACCUUUUGGAUAAGGGGGAUUUUGGCACUCAAAAAGAAGCUGCUUGGGCCAUAAGUAACUUAACAAUUAGUGGAAGGAAAGAUCAAGUGGCUUACCUUAUCCAACAAAAUGUUAUCCCACCUUUUUGCAACUUGCUGACUGUAAAAGAUGCACAAGUUGUGCAAGUAGUACUCGAUGGACUAAGUAAUAUAUUAAAAAUGGCUGAAGAUGAGGCAGAAACCAUAGGCAAUCUUAUAGAAGAAUGUGGAGGGCUGGAGAAAAUUGAACAACUUCAAAAUCAUGAAAAUGAAGACAUCUACAAAUUGGCCUAUGAGAUCAUUGAUCAGUUCUUCUCUUCAGAUGAUAUUGAUGAAGACCCUAGCCUUGUUCCAGAGGCAAUUCAAGGCGGAACAUUUGGUUUCAAUUCAUCUGCCAAUGUACCAACAGAAGGGUUCCAGUUUUAGAAAGAUGUUGUGGAAGUUAGGUACAAUGCAGCACUGAGAUAUAUAUAUAUAUAUGUGUGUGUGUAUAUAUAUAUAUAUAUACAUAUAUAUAAAAAGGUUUGAUCCAUCAAGCUUGGCUCAUGGGAUCUGCUGCUGCAUUAAAUCGGGAAAGAAAAUGUGAAGAUUUCAUUUGGAAUCACAGAAAAUGCCCAAAUGAGGUCAAGAUGGCGAGUGGGUGCGAGUGAGAAUGAGUGGCAAAAUGUAAUGAAAACUUUACAUGAAUGCUUAUUUAGGUUGUUCAAAGUAAAAAGGGCUACAGGUCACAGAUCGUCAGUGCCUGAGAAAGAACAUUGACUUACUCUAUAUCAAUUGAGGGGAAAGUGCAGUACCGUCAUCUUCAAGCCUUGUAAGCAUAAAAGAGAAUAGGCUGCCCAUAUAAGUCAAAGGAAAAUGAGCCCAGGCCUUGCUAUGAAGCAGUGUGUGAAUGGACAAUGUUGAAUGAAUGUCUGGCUCAGUGAUGGAGAGCCAGGUUCAUCUUUGAAAUCUAGGGCUCUUCACUCAUGAAGCAGACUCCUAGUCCUGGAGUGACUGUGUACGAGAGCGUGGUUGUGGUGCUGUAUGUGAACGCAUGCAAGCUUGAUUCACCUUCAGGGGGCUGAUAACCUAGUAAAUCAUCAAAAUGAGAUCAUAAGUGUUAAUGUACACUGGACAUGAAAACAAAGACUGGUUUAGCAGCAGACAUUGGUUUACUCUGCAGCCUGUGUUUUCUGUUUCCCCCUUUCCCACCUCCUUCCCCCCACCCAAUCCUUUUUUUUUUCUUUUUUGCUUUUCUUUUCUUUUUUUUUAGUUUUUAUUUACUUUACCUAGUAUGCCUUUUUUUAGUUGCUUCUCAAGUCAGAAAACUUUUCAGGAAGGUUUCCCUGUGCAUUUGCACCAGAUGAAUGUUUGAUGCUAUGAAAAGCUUUCCAUAUCAUCAAAACUAAUUUGUGUAGAUUUUUGCAUGAAAAAAAUCAUAAAUUUCCCUCAAAAUAGACUGUGUUGCAGUACACAAGUUGCCAUAAUAGUAUAAAACAGUAAAAUGUGCUUAAAAGGCCAUCCUUUUCAUUUUCAGAGAUAACAUAAAGAUCUUUGCAUGAGGUAAAUCUACAGCAUAGUUCAUUUUUAGAUUUUGUUGAGUCCUGUAAAGAAGAAGAAGAAAAAAGUUUCAGUUGUGGUAGAAUACCGUGCUGUGUUUAAAUGUUACUUGUUUUCAAACUUUGUUUUCUAUGAAAAUGAUAUGGAAACUUCUAAAAUGGAAUUUGGUGCAUAUGUACUGCUGAAUAAAGACCGAUGAAGAGGUUUGAGUAGAUGUACAAAUCAAGUAAUGGUUUGAACACCUUUAAUAAUAUGCCUAAUCUGUUCAAUUGUUUUAGAAUCUUUUUAUCUUAGAUGUAGGCAGCCAUGAACAAUCUAUUUUGAGCCACUUUAGGGAGAAAACUUUGUAUUUUUAAAACUUGCAUAAAAGUUAUGCAAGUGGUUUUUAUAAAUUGGAAUAAUACCUCAGUUUUGAGGUUAUGCACACUAAAUUAAAUGUGACAUAAAUUAAUUUGUACAAAAAGAACUCUUUAUAAGGUGGCUCAUUGUAGGAAAUCCUGUGCCUUCCCCUUUGAGCACAAGUGUUGCAUGAACAACAGUUUGCUAUAAGAAACAUACCAGAUUAGCCACCAUUAGCAUCUAUAUCUACUUUGUGUUUAAAAAUCAACUGGUAAUUCUGAAACACUGUAGAAUGGAUAAAAAUUAUUUUGUGAUCAUAACUCUUUGUUGAACUAGAGUAUUUUUGCAGCAUUCCUUGUCAUCAGAAACAUGGUUAAAGUUUAAAACUAGAAGCAGCAGAAAACUAGCUUGUAAAAUUUAUCCAAGUAGAGUGCAGGCUAGGCUGUCUUGGGGAAAUAAACAUUAAAACUUAAAGCAAUGUUUUACAUGGGGUGUGUGUGUGUGGUGUGUGGAUUUUUUUUUUUUUAUAAAGUUAGAGUAUAAUUCAAUGGCUUACAUUAGCUUCCUGUCUUUUUACCUAGAACCAGCAUAAUAAGAAAUUUCUUUGGUUCUGUCAUUUCAGUAUGGACAUAUUAAUAUUUUAGCCCACUGAGUUUGUCCAGUUGACACCAUCAGUGCUUCAGUUUUCUCUCUAUCCAAAGCAAGGUUUUAACUUUCCUUCAUUCUCCAGUAAAACAGACCGAGACAACUUGAACUAUAUUUUGAGUAUUGCUAUAUCUUCAACAUAUAGCUCCAAAUGAUGGAUUGUAUACAAAGCAUAGUACAGAAGGUUUCAGUAAUUGGAAGGUGAACACAGCAAUGCUUUACAUAAUUUGUGUUUUUUAGUAAAAAAUAUUGGAUUCAAAGUAAGCCAAUGAGCUUGUAUACAAAUUUUAUAUACAAAUUAUUGUAUAGAACAGUGAUAUGGAAAAUAGGUAAGGGUGAUAUUAAUAUCUCUGGGUAUAAGGACUACCUUAUCGUUUAAAUAUUUUAUUUCCAUCUAUAGCCUAAUAUAGAACAUUGAUUUUCUAGUAGAAAUUCUGGGAAGGGCUUUUCUGUCUCUGAAAUUGAUUCAGUACAGUUGACAGUUCAUCACGGUUACCUGGUUAAACACUUUUUUUUUUUUUUUAAUUCUCCAGUGAUCUAGGAAAUUGUUUCAUUUUUAACACAGGCUUAUUUCUGAUGGGGAUGGGGGCAUAGAAUAAUAUGCCUAAUAAGCUAAACGUUCUUAACGUUUCAUGUCUUAAACUGUCUUUUUGAACAUUGAGACCACCUCAAGUGCUGUAAAAAUAAGAAUGUUAUAUUAGGGGUGUGUGAGACGCCCUAGUCUAAAAUCUAUCUUUAAAUAUAUUUCCUUUGUAAUUUUCAAAGACUUCAGUAAUUGUGUGUUAUGGUGGAAAUAAUACUUUCCAUUGGUCCACAUUGCUCUGGACCAAACCUGGAGCAUUUCUAUAAUUAGAGCUAUCUAUGAAUCAUUAAAAAUGGAUCUAGAAUAAUUUUGGGGAGAGGGAGUGUAUCAUUUAGUUUAGGCUUACCUCAGCAGCACUUCAUAGGGUGAGGAGUUGUUUGUUUCUUUAAAGGUAUAACUGCAUUGUAAAAUGACUGGGUUUAUUGUAACAGUAAUUUAUGGGGGCACCCUUUUUGGAUUCUCCAUUGCCUCAGUUUCCUCAAGGAAAAAGUUACAGAGAUUAAGCUAAAUUUUGAAUUUAGAGAAUAACUGCUGUGUAAUUUUGGUAUAAUUACCAUAAAUUUAGUGUCUUAAAACACAACAUACAUUAUUUCACAAUUUCUGUAGGUCAAGAGUGUAGUUAGGUUUUCUGCUCAGGGUCUCACAAGGCUGCAAUAAAGGUGUCAGCCAGAGCUGCAGUCUUAUCUGAAGCUAGGGGGUCCUCUUUUAUGCACAUAUGGCAAAAUCCAUUGCCUAGCAACUGAAGAAAUCAUGGGAACUUCUUCAAGGCCAGCAAGAGAAUCUCUGAUCUCAGGGAAGGCCUUAAGCGCUUUUUUAAAGGUCUCACCUGAUUAGAUCAGGCCACCUACCCACCAGGGUGAUCUCCCUUUUGAUUAACCCAAAGCCAAACUGAUGAGGUACCUUCAUUACCCCUGCAAAAUCCCUUCACCUUUGCCCUGCAUUGUAGUCCAAUCACAGGGGUGAUACGCAUCAUAUUCAAAGAUCCUGUUCACAGUCAAGGGAGGGGGUUAUAUGGAGUAUGUAUACCAGGGAAUCUUGGGAGCCAUCUUAAGAGUUCUUCCUAUGACAAGGACUCAACUAUUUAGAACUGGAACAAUUUACAAGUGAUAGCCUUAUAUAGUUAUCAUAGCAAGCUUAUUUGGGGAUCAAGGUUGCCUCUGAGAACCUAAUGAAAACUGGACCAGCUUCCCCAAAAAGUGUAUAUACAUGGUAGUUUUUCAUACAGUUUUAGGGGAUUCAUAAGAGUCCAUGAAUUACAGUCUGUCCCAACCCUUCCCUUUAGAUGAUGAGUUGUUGAGGUGACUUGCCCAAGGUCACACAGCUACUAAGGGCCAAAUAAAGCCCACAUCUCAACUCCCAUACUGCCCAGGGCUUCUAAUUACUAUUCUAAAGGUAAUCUAAAUUCAUUUAAAUUUGUGAACCAAUGCAAAAAAAUGUGAAUGUAGCUUUUUGGAUAUUUUUUUUGUUUACUAAGGAAUGGGUAACAUUGUUAUAGAAGCUUGCCUAAGAGUUUUGAAAUUAGUUGACCUUUUUGAGUUUCCAAAAUUGAAUCUUCCAUUGUAGCUAUUAAAGUGAACUAUAAAUAGGCCAACUUUAAUUGUUAACUCCUCGGGUUUGGUGGAUUAUCUACCAUUUAUAUAUAAAAUUUCAGUUAGAAUCCACCAUUGGCGUUUUGAAGGCCAAGAUAGCUGAGUAUCUUAUCCUUUUUGUAACUUCUUGAUUAUUUUACUUAUUGGCAAAAUUCAUUAACUGUCAGCCAAUAAUUUAAUAUUAUGGGAGGAAAAAAUUUUGCCCAGAUAUCUGAGGCAAUACUCCCAAACACUAACAAACUGAUGCCUAACAAACUUGACAUUUUGAACACUUAAAGUUUUCCCUAAACUUUUUAAUAAGCACAUUAAUAAAGUAUGCUUUUAAAUAUAUAUGUACAAUAAUUUUUAAAAGUUGCUGCAAGAUGCCUUCAAAUCAAUAUGCACGUUGGUGGCAUUAGUGCAGUCUUCUAUUUUUAUUUUUUUGAGACACAGUCUCGCUCUGUGGCCCAGGCUGGAGUGUAGUGGCGCAAUCUCGGCUCACUGCAACCUCUGCCUCAAGGGUUCAAGCAAUUCUGCCUCAGCCUCCUGAGUAGCUGGGAUUACAGGAGUACGCUACCACGCCUGGCUAAUUUUUGUAUUUUUAGUAGAAAUGGGGUUUCACCGUAUUGGCCAGGCUGGUAUUGGAAUCCUGACCGCAAAUGAUCUGCCCACCUCGGCUUCCCAAAGUGCUGGGAUUACAGGCGUGAGCCACUGCGCCCAACCAGCCUUAAUUCUUAAUAAAGGAAGUUGAAAAAUAAUGAACAUUGGUAAAACUAUUCUAGUGUGAUCAGAAGCAAAUUUGGACUGUAGUGUCAAAUUGAUAAAAAACUAAGCACACCAAUCAUGUAUAAGAAAAGUAGAUUUAACAUUUUUUUCCCUAAACACUUAACCCAGAAGUUAACAAUAAUCUUGAAAAUUCCUUUUAAAUCCAGGCCCUUUAGGUGAUGGCAGUUUGACUCAGGAUGUCCAAGUCCAGUGUAUUUUCAAUAAAAUUGACUUGACAGCUACUGCUCUGGGUGUAAGAGCAGUUGACUGUGAGGAAAAGUAAAUGGUUCUACAGAUUCUUUAUGAUCUACCUCCCACCAGAGGACUGCAGUACUCCCUUGUUAUUUAUAUUUUCUGCCCCAAUUUUUGCCUUCUCCACAAAUUUUAUACCUUUUGUAGCUGCCUACUCCAGAUUACUUCACCUUUCCAGACUAUCAGUUCUUCCACUUUUAUUCUUCAUAAAGAAAAUUCCAAUAACCUGUUUCACUUAGGUUUUUCUAUUACUCUUCAAGCAUGAAUCCUAAUUUCCCUGACUAUAUCUUACCUCUGAUCUCCAUAACUGAUGGAUUCCUAUCCUAGACUAUGUUACUCUAAUAUUACCCAAGAUUUUCUCCAGCCUGUUUUUACUCUUACUUUGAAACAGCUGUUUAAAAUGACUCGUAAUCUGCUUAAAUCUACAUGCUUUUUGUGGUUCUCAAUCCAGUUACCUACCUUCCAGAUAAUUCCCUCACUGUCCUGUCCUCUCCAUUCCUCUGAUGUUUAAGCCCUGUGAGCCACCUUUCCCCCAUCCUUUGUGCAUAGUUACCAUUUUACUCUUUCUUGUUGCCCAGGCAGGAAUGCAGUGGUGCCAUCUUGGCUCACUGCAACCUCCACCUCCUAGGUUCAAGCGAUUCUCCUGCCUCAGCCUCCUGAGUAGCUGGGACCACAAGCGUGCACCACCACGCCCGGCUAAUUUUUGUAUUUUUAGUAGAGAUGGGGUUUCACCACGUUGGCCAGGCUGGUCUCGAACUCCUGACCUCAGAUGAUCCACCCUCCUUGGCCUCCCAAAGUGCUGGGAUUGCAGGCGUGAGCCACCGCCUGGCCACCAUUUUACUCUUUUUAGGUACAGUAAUCUAAUAUCCAAAGUCUUGGACUCAGCUAAAGAGGGUAUUUACCUUAAAAAAAAAAAAAAAAAGACUCCAUCUUUUGAUUCAUAAUUGUGGUGGGGGCGGGGAAUCAAGACAACCUUAGUCACUUUGGUAUUACCAUAAUUCUUGUCUUUUCAGGGUUGUCCUGUUCAGCUGCAUAAAACAUCAUGUAUUCUAGGUAUUUCCUACCUUCACUUACAUUUUUACUUGCCGAUGUGCUGCCUUCAUAAAUGGGUAUAUUCCGCCACACAUCUAGUAAGCCCCCAAUGCAGUACACAAUGUGUAUCACUGAUAAAACUCGCACUUCUGCCAUGUCAGUAUUAUAUUCAGUUGAGUGGUCUUUAGCAUAGUGGCAGUCCUAGUCAUCCUAACCUUUUAGUUAAGGUAAAAUUACAUAUGUUUAUAGAACUCAUAUAGACAAGCUAGUUUUUAAAAUCUUCCUUUUAACCAGUUUAGGAUGAUCUAGGAUAGCUAAGUUACCUACAUGGUGACUGUUCGGUCUAAUUCAGAAACAGAAGUACUAAAAGAAUACUAAAAAGUUUUUACCCAUUAUCUCUAUCCCUGUUUUCUUUUUGCAAUUCUCAGCUGCAGGGAGCAAGAAAAUACACAGCAGAUAGGAAAUGUUUGUUUGCAUCCUGGCUUUCUCAACCGCACUUUACGUCCUUGAAUAUUCUAGAUAUUUACUCCUUCAAGAAGUCAGGAGUAUAUCCAGGCCUACCUAUCAUCCUUGCCAUCCCCAUUAACCCUCAUUUUUCAGUAUGUGUUUUACAUUUAUGGUUAUUUUUCAGUCUAUAGUAUCUGUUCACUCAUUGCUCUAUCACAUCUGAGUUUCUCCGUCUUUCUUUCCACUAGAUUGUAAGCUCCUUAAGGGCAAGGUCGGCAUAUAAGCAAAGUUCUGUAAACACCGUGAAGGUACCAUGAGUUCUAUGGGUACUCAAUAAAUGCUUGUGAUAAUGA